GCCCCUGGCCACCAAGCGCCUCCGUGGACACGCACUUCCUGCGAGGGCUCCGUGCGCACCUUGGCCGAGCCGAACCGAGCCGAGUCCUGUCCUUCCAGGCCGUUCGCAAUGGUGGAUGAGUUGGUGCUGCUGCUGCACGCGCUCCUGAUGCGGCACCGCGCCCUGAGCAUCGAGAACAGCCAGCUCAUGGAACAGCUGCGGCUGCUGGUGUGCGAGAGGGCCAGCCUGCUGCGCCAGGUACGUCCGCCGAGCUGCCCGGUGCCCUUCCCCGAAACGUUUAAUGGCGAGAGCUCCCGGCUCCCCGAGUUUAUCGUGCAGACGGCGUCUUACAUGCUCGUGAACGAGAACCGAUUCUGCAACGACGCCAUGAAGGUGGCAUUCCUAAUCAGCCUCCUCACCGGGGAAGCCGAGGAGUGGGUGGUGCCCUACAUCGAGAUGGAUAGCCCCAUCCUAGGUGAUUACCGGGCCUUCCUCGAUGAGAUGAAACAGUGCUUUGGCUGGGAUGACGACGAAGACGACGACGACGAAGAAGAGGAGGAUGAUUAUUAGGCCCUCGACCCUCGGGCCUCGGGGGGGAGGGCCCUGCACGCCGCCACCCCCUCCCCGCAGCCCUCACCCCGCCAGGAGCCACUGCUCUCCCCCUUGCCCUCCGGUCCCCUUACCUACCCGCGCCCGUCUGCUCUCUCUCUUCAUUUCUCCGUAGUGCUUGUCUUUGUUCCAGGAAUAGCGCUCCAGUUACCUGCUGCUGGGGUCGGGGCUGGAGCCUCACUCACUCGGAAGUGCUUGGAAGUGUCAUCUACCCUGGCCAUCCCCGGGAUCCCUCCCCUGCUAAUCUGAACUGUGUCCUGAACCCCAGCUAUUGGCCAGGCCCCUGUUACAAACUGCGCAGACCACCCGUAGCCCUGCUGCUGCCACCUGCCCUGCUGCCAGGCUUACAUCUUCCCAGAGAACUAUGCUGCCACUUCACAUCCACUCACCACAUCCCACCUACAGACUACCACCUUUCGAGAUCAGGACCAACCUGGAAAAUGCCAGAGUUGGCUAUGCCUUUUCAGACAUUGAUUUGGACAGCUCACCAACCCCUGAAGGGGCCGUUCAGCCUGGUUAGUUUUCUACCUACUCCGAGUGUCCUCCCCUGCCCCACCAGAUUGCUGCAGGGGCGCGGUGUGCCUGGCAGCCAAAUUGUUGACACUUCUUUUUUCCUAUGCACUGGUUUUACACAGCUGUCAUUUUUCUUUCAAAAUUGCAGCAGUCCCACAGAUGUGUGCAUUUGGACAAAUAGUACUUAAAAACAAAACAAACAAGCACUCAGCCCAGCUCCUCAAUACUACCUGGAAAAAGCAUUGGCAUUAUUUUCAAUAAAUAUCAAGCACUAAAAAAAGAAAUGAUUGUCUUUUAAUGGUUAAGUGCUAUCACUGGCCUCUACCACUGUCACUCUGACUACCAUUAUUCCCGUGGAAAUCAGGGAAUACAACCAAUCCUAGUAUUCCCCGCUGUCAUCUCCAGGCUGCUGGGGACAGCUACCUCAGGGCUUUGUCAGGGUUCUGAUGCUCCCUUCACCAACGCAUUUCUUAAAGCCCUGGCAAAGGGUGUGUUCUCUGGGUCCUCCAGGGUGGCGUGGUUAAGGGUUGGCUGAGCAGACGGCAAAGAGAGCAGUAUUAAUAAUUAGACCAUAACAAUAGGCGUAAACCUGGACAUAUAUAUGUAAUGCUCCUAAUUCUCUGAGCUUUUGGAUUCCUUAACACUGUGCCAGGGAAGUUCUGCCCCUUAAUCCUUAUUGCCUAUGUGCAGCUGUUGAGUUCAGACUCCAGAGAGCCAACAUAGUAGAUUGUCACUUUCAAACUCCAAAUAGCCAACAUGUCACUUUCAGGUGCUCCAGCUAACAUUAAGUCCCGGAUCCUGGGCAAGUGCACCCAUAAAGAUAUAGCCUGAUCUUAACAAACAUUUCGUUCUCCUUGGACAGACAUCCUUAGAAUUCCCACUCAUAGAUGUGUCCCAGAUUCCUCCCUAUGGAAAUUAGCAAGAUGCUUGGUUAUCUCUUAAAUCAGACCUUGUACUGCUAUCUAGGGGCUAUGCUGAGAUCUCUGGGCCUGGAGGGUUCAGAGCAGUGAAGGGGGUGGCUGCUGAGAAGAAGCUGCAUACCUGUGUGAGGCCAUUGCUCCAGGUUAAGUCAUUGAAAUGUUUAAUGCAGAGCAGCUUGGUUGGGGAUUUGAGAGGACUGCCUCUUAGAAAGGUUUAGGAGGAUAUGAGGGGUUCAGAGUUCUCUUUUAUAUCUGUCCAGAUGUCCUCAUUGUACCAUGUCUGGAGCCAACUUGACUUUAUAACCUUUAAUUAAUUUAGAUAACACAUUUCCGUACUGUUUAAGGCCUUUUGAGGCAAGAUAUUGUAUUUGUACUGGUAAACCUCAGUGUUGAUUAAAUGAGAUAUGGGUCUUCAUAUUAAUCACCUCAUAGGUGCGGAUUAAAUGAGAUCAUACCCAUGAAGCAUUUAGAACUUUCCCUGCUACAUGGUGAGCACUCAGCAAACCAUGGGCUGUUACUCCUGGGCCAGGGAACAGAAGUCUCAGAAAGCAAGUCUCUGACUCUGAGCCUGGCUUUAGUAGGAAAAUGUCAGCGUGAAGAGGAGCAGAGCAGGUUCAGGGAGAAUGGAAAUGAGAGCAUGAUAAGACCCCAUUUACUUUUUGGAGUCUUAUAUGAAGCAAGAAACAAAGCUGUUUUACGUGGUGGACAGGCAAAGUUCAGGGUAGGAGUUAUAUCUCACCCCUAGGAUAGCUGUUUCUGGAGGGUGGGGACAGGGUUGCGUAUGACUUAAUAAAAGAGGCUGAGGCUUGGGUGGAAAUGAGAUCUGGGGCUCUUCAGGGAGCUGCCGCCUCCAAAUCUGAAUCAAGGAGACAGCUGGUUAUUUAGAAUUCAUUGAUCACUUCUCCCAGUCUCCUUGGAAAAUAUACAAAACCCCUUGGAAGAGAGAGAUUAUAUUUGAGACAUAAUAUGUGUGAGGCCAGAUAAUUACACUUUCUUCCUAACUAGAAAGGCCUUGAAUUGGGGAUAAAUGUGGAAAAGUGAGCAAGAUCUAAAAGGUAAAGGAUCCAGUGAGACCAAAAGUCAUUUAUUCCAAACUGAUUAUGGCCCAGUUAUGCUGAGUGGAGUUACAGAAACAUCUUUGAAUAAAAUGUGAUCUCUGCCUUCAUAGCGAGUCCAGUCUGCUGCUUUUACUGUGCCCUGGGUCAGAACUUUGAUGAUUAGUUACAGGAAAGGGCCAGGAAGAGAAUCUGGGCUGUGAUUAGAUCUGGGAAUGACCUUUCUGGGGUGGAAGUUGAGGACAUAUGAGUAGGUGUUCUGUGGAGGAAGGGAGGUUCAGUAAGGAUGCCAUGCCAAGGCAGCAUCUGAAUGGCAUCUGGGAGAACUAGGCCAGGGAGCUUCUGUGAUCUGAAGUGUACAUUUCCUGAGUAUGUGUGCAUGUGCACAUGAGCUUGCUGUGACCCAGUAUGUGUGUGCUCUGUGUGUGUGUGUGUUAAGUGAUGUCCUUCUUACAUCAUGGACAAACAGGUUAUGCUGUGAGAUGCAGAAAAGGGAUUCUGGUUACUUUGGGGGCAGAUUCUGCAAUAAAAGCGCAGAUACUGGCAAGGGCUCCACCACCCAGGGAGGAAUUCAUGAUAAUGGCAUAAAGCAUGGCAAAAAAGAAGGAAGAAGUAGAAGUAUGUCUAAGGAUAAAAGUGCCACUUUGAUCAAAACUAUUAAAAAUAGGUAGGAAUGCUGAAUAAAUAUGAACUUAGACCCUGAAUUCUCAUUUUGGGCGUAAUAGACUUGAAAUGGCCGCUGAAAUUAUACUAUCAAUGAAAUGAAAUUAGUCAUAUUAAAUGUCGUAAUCAUUUAAUCGUAUUAAAUAUACCAAUAUA